AGUUCCAAGUAGGUAAUCCUUCUGAGAAGUCCCACCUUUCUGAGCAGCUGUGUUUGAAGAAAGCUAGUGGGAAAAGUUCCAGGAUUACAUGUCAGGAAACUACAAGAGGUAGAAACAUUUGUUGAUUUACCAGUGUUUUUAACUUCCUGCUGGGCUGAAAACUGCUUGUUUCGUGGAAAAGCAAAACUUGACAGCAAACAUCUAAAAUGAAGAGCUCCCAAACUUUUGAGGAACAAACGGAAUGCAUUGUGAACACUCUACUCAUGGACUUCUUGAGCCCAACAUUGCAGGUUGCCAGCCGGAACCUAUGCUGUGUAGAUGAAGUAGAUUCAGGAGAGCCUUGUUCUUUUGAUGUGGCUAUCAUUGCUGGUCGCCUUCGGAUGUUGGGUGACCAGUUCAACGGAGAAUUGGAAGCUUCUGCCAAAAACGUCAUUGCAGAAACCAUUAAGGGACAGACAGGAGCUAUACUCCAGGACACUGUGGAAUCUCUCAGCAAGACCUGGUGUGCUCAGGAUUCCAGCUUAGCUUAUGAGAGAGCUUUUCUGGCAGUGUCAGUGAAACUUCUUGAGUACAUGGCUCACAUUGCUCCUGAAGUAGUGGGACAGGUGGCUAUCCCCAUGACGGGUAUGAUCAAUGGGAACCAAGCCAUCCGGGAGUUCAUCCAGGGCCAGGGAGGUUGGGAAAAUCUGGAGAGCUGAAGAGUUGGAGCUAUUCACGAGACUGAACAUCACUUCCUUGUUGACUGAUUGGGUGAUUGAUUCCUGGGAAUUCAAACAAACAAAUAAAAAAGCACUUUUUUCAUUUUAUCAGAACUGAACUUAGCUGAAUAAGUUAUUUUUUACUGAUUGUUAAAGUUGGGAGCAGCUGCCAGAGGCCUGCAGAGUUGGUUUUUGUUUUGUUUUGUUUUGUCAACUUAAUGCAAACCACAGAGAUUUUCUACUUUCUGUUUUCACAUGAGUUUUAAUGAGGUUCUGUUGAAGCAAAGACCCCUAGACACAAAGUAAUGACUUGUUAGUAGUGGAAUUAUAAGCAACAGGGCAGGCCUUUGCUGGAGGUAUUUUGAGAGAAAGGGAGAACAAUGGAAACUAUUUCUUCAGAUGUAGCCCUGUCUUUUGGUAAGAAUUGUGCCUACUAAUUUUGCAAUUUAAAGGAUUUCAGGAAGCUUUUUGGUUGAAAAAUCUUGUUUUUUUUUUUUUAGACGUAGUCUCACUCUGUCACCCAGGCUGGAGUGCAGUGGUGCGAUCUCAGCUCACUGCAAGCUCCACCUCCCGGUUUCACUCCAUUCUCCUGCCUCAGCCUCCUGAGUAGCUGGGACUACAGGAGCCCGCCAUCACGCCCGGCUAAUUUUUUGUAUUUUUAGUAGAGAUGAGGUUUCGCCGUGUUAGCCAGGAUGGUCUGGAUCUCCUGACCUCGUGAUUCGCCCGCCUUGGCCUCCCAAAGUGCUGGGAUUACAGGCGUGAGCCACCACGCCCGGCCUAAAAUCUUGUUAUUUUAAGUUGAGCAUUUUCAUUCAAAAUCAUCCCUAAACUUCAUGUUAAUUUCACCUGAGAAGGACUAUUUUAUGCAUUUUAGAGGUUGGAAGCAAAAAACAAACAAACAAACAAAAACAGUUGUUUCUACUAGGAAGGUCAAAGAAAAUAAAAGUUACUCCAUUUUUACUGCCACAGGAUGCAGGAAGUGCUGGCCCACAUCUAGGACAGCAAGGCCACCCCAGCUUAGAUGAAGCUAGCUGCAUAACACAAAGCUUUAAAAGUGUGGUUCACACACCACUUGUGGACCUUAUUGAAUUGCUGAUUCGCAUUCCUAGAGAUUCUGAUUCUGUAGGGGUAGGCUGGAGCCUAGGAACCUACCUUUUAAACUAGUUCCAUAGGUGAUUCUGAUGUACAUAUAGAGUGUGACAGCCAUCACUAUAGAGAAUAGAUUGAUAAAUUACAACCCACGCGUCAAAUCUGGCUUGCUGUCUUAUUUUGUAAAUAAAGUUUUAUUGGAAUAGAGCAACAUUCACUUGUUUACAUAUUGUCCAUGGCCGCUUUUGUGCUACAAUGGCAGAGUUGAAUGAUUAUAGAAGACCAUAUGGCUGGUUAAGUCCAAAAUAUUUACUAGCUGGCCCUUUACAGAAAAAGUUGGCUGACCCCUUCUCUAAAUCAACAUUUCUCCUUGGUAACUGAAACUCUAUUACAGUCCUGACAAUUCCAGCAAACACAGCUGUAGAUAGGGUUUAAACUCAAAGAUAUUUAACUCUUCUUUGGGAACUUAGUCUCCAUAUGUUUGUUAGUUCUUGCAUAAUCCACAGUUUCUCUGGGUCUUCAGCCAAUCAGAGAGCUCUGUAGCUCCUGAGUAGUCCAUUUCUCUGGCCCUACAAGUGAGAGUGAUUGGAAGCAAAGCUUAUGAUUUGUAUGAUCUUGUAUCUCAAAAUAGUCCUUAAUGAUCUAAUAGAUUAGUAGGCAGUCAUCAGGUAGAGACUCCAAAAACCAGACUACUUUCCUAAAUAUCAAGAAGAAAGGCAUUGCUACAGUGAUUCAUGAAAAGCAGCAUUAAUAACUUUGGCUAAAGUUUAACAAAGCUAACCACUUCCCCUCUAUCAGCCAGCCAUCUAUGUAUCUCCUCUAAAUGCAGAGAAGUAAAUAUGUAGUGCUGUUAAUACAUUUUUGCUUUUUAAAGUUAUGCUUUGUCCUGGCGCAGUGGCUCAUGCCUGUAAUCCCAGCACUUUGGGAGGCCAAGGCGGGUGGAUCACCUGAGGUUAGGAGUUUGAGACCAGCCUGGCCAACAUGGUGAAACCCUGUCUCUGCUAAAAAUACAAAAAAUUAGCCAGGCUUGGUGGCACGUGCCUGUAAUGCCAGCUACUCAGGAGGCUGAGGCAGGAGAAUCACUUGAACCUGGGAGGCGGAGGUUGCUGUGAGCUGAGUUCGCGCCAUUGCACUCCAGCCUGGGCUACAAAAGCGAAACUGUCUAAAAAAAAAAAAAGAAAAUAAAUAAAGUUAUGCUUUUUCCUCUAUUCCUAGUUAAAUCACAACAAGUUAGUAAUCCAUAAAUGAUGUGUCCUGUUUCUCUUUAGUAGAAAUUAUAUUUUUGGCUACCAGUUAAGAAACUUGUACUCCUUUGUCCCUUAUGUUACUAUAAACUCAAGAUGAUGAGUUUUGUGGUAUUUGACUUCAUAGGCAAAAUCAAAAUUUUUACUUUGUUGCUAUUCUGUUUUAUGAAAUAAACUUCUGUCUAUGCAUUUGAACUAAGUUUCAGCAAAUUCAAUCUAAAUUGAAUAAUUCCAGCUCCCAGUUUUAUCCUAUGUUGCUCAUAAAACAGUUCCAAGUAUACUGCAUUAUCUUGAGAUUUGAAGAUAUGGUGCCCACGGGGAUUAUACUAGGCAAAUGCGUUAAGCAGCUCUGGCCUAGGUGUUGUGUAUUUUAAGAGACUCUAUCUUAGGAGAGCUUAAGUGAUUGGGCUGCAGGAAGAAGACAUUGUAACCCAGGAAUUAAAAAUGGAUUCAGAUUGCCUGAUUUUAACACUUUAGUUUCACCAUAGGCUAAUUAUGUGACAUUGGGCAAGAGACAUAAUUCUUCUGUACCUUAGUUUCUACAUUUGUAAAAUAGAGAUGAUUUGGUAACUUAUUAAUAAGAUUUUUGUGAGAGAUAAAUAAAACAAAUACAUUUUGUAAAGGGUGAGUACUUGGAAUAUUUUAAACACUGUGCCAUUAGCAAUUUGGAAUUCUGUGUUAUGCAGUUCAUAAGGUUCUAGCUUGACUUUUUUCUCUCUCCAUUAACCCUGUCUCUCACAGAUGCAAACCACUCUUAAUGGCUUUACUUUCACAUCAAUGUGAGUGAUUCCUAAAUAUGAUUUAUUUCCCUUCUCAAUUCCAUACCCACAGAUGCUUAUUAUUUAUUUAUGUGUACCUUUCUUAUCCCCAUACUCUCCCUGUUUGCGAUACAACUAGCUCAAAACCUCAGUCAUUUUUACCUUGUCUCUCUCUCUCCAGUCCAACUCACCCAACUAGUUUUUCUCAUUUGUUACUUCAUUUUUGUCCUGGUUCUUCUACCAGAUUUAUUAGCAACUGCCUGGACUAUUAAUAAAGCCUCCUACUUAGGCUUUCAAUAGAUUGUUCUGUUCCUGCUCCAUUCCAGUCUGUCCUAUAUACUGCCAUCAGAUUGAUCAAAGCUGUGGUUUCUUUGUCUAUUAUUUUGAUUCAUUUUUAGAUAUGGUAUCAUUCAUUUUUAAAUUUAACAUACCAAUGAAGAUUACAAGACUUAAACAUCUUAUCAGAAGGGGGCAUUUAUUUUUUAAAUCAAGAAAUAACUUUCCAAAAGCAUUGCUUUGAAUGCCAUUCUCUUAAAGUCCUUCAGUGGAACUUUUGAGUGUGAUUAGACAUGUUCAUUAUCUUGAUUGUAGUGAUUUUAUGGGUGAUGAUUUCACACCAACUUAUCAAACUGCAUACUUUGAAAUGUGUAGUUUAUUGUACAUCAGCACUACCUUAAUAAGGUUGUUUUUUUUAAAAAAAAAAAAAAAACCUUCAGCUGCUCCCUACUGUUCAUCAAAUAACAGUCUGAUAUUCAAAUUCCCCCAGUAUCUGGCCCUAACUGCCCUAUAUAGCCUUAAUCAAUCAUGAUUCUCCUCUACAAUCCCAAUGCUCUAGUAUAACCGAGCCAGUCACUAAAGCUGCCCUCCUCCUACUGUUCCCUAUGUUUCAUAUUCCUUUUUCUGAGGCUCUACCUGUAGACAUCUUCAAGACCCAACCCAACUGUCAUGAAGCCUUCUCCAUGAAGGCUAUCCAUAUAACCAGAAUAAGAAGUGGUCUUUGCCUCCUUGAACUUUUGUUUGUACCACUUUUAUGUUUCUUAUCCAAAAAAUGGCCUUAAGUUGUAAUUAUCUGUAUAGUCAUCUUCCCCACUAGGAUAAAGGAUUGCUGAAUGAUACAAUUUGUUGUAUACUUCUGUAACACCCCUCCUCUUCAUUAUCUGGCAUGUACAUCGAUAUUAAAAAUAUUCAUUAAAUGAAUGAAUAGCUGAUUGACUCA